GCUCCCGGAGGCCGCAGCCUCCAGCUCCGCUCGCGCUCUCGCCGCUCCUGCCGGCUCGCCCGGCCCCGCGCUCCGCCGUCUCCUCGCCGCCCGCCCCUCCGCCAGCCCCGGGGACCGCGCGGCCGCAGCCUGAGCCAGGGCCCCCUCCCUCGUCAGGACCGGGGCAGCAAGCAGGCCGGGGGCAGGUCCGGGCACCCACCAUGCGAGGCGAGCUCUGGCUCCUGGUGCUGGUGCUCAGGGAGGCUGCCCGGGCGCUGAGCCCCCAGCCCGGAGCAGGUCACGAUGAGGGCCCAGGCUCUGGAUGGGCUGCCAAAGGGACCGUGCGGGGCUGGAACCGGAGAGCCCGAGAGAGCCCUGGGCAUGUGUCAGAGCCGGACAGGACCCAGCUGAGCCAGGACCUGGGUGGGGGCACCCUGGCCAUGGACACGCUGCCAGAUAACAGGACCAGGGUGGUGGAGGACAACCACAGCUAUUAUGUGUCCCGUCUCUAUGGCCCCAGCGAGCCCCACAGCCGGGAACUGUGGGUAGAUGUGGCCGAGGCCAACCGGAGCCAAGUGAAGAUCCACACAAUACUCUCCAACACCCACCGGCAGGCUUCGAGAGUGGUCUUGUCCUUUGAUUUCCCUUUCUACGGGCAUCCUCUGCGGCAGAUCACCAUAGCAACUGGAGGCUUCAUCUUCAUGGGGGACGUGAUCCAUCGGAUGCUCACAGCUACUCAGUAUGUGGCGCCCCUGAUGGCCAACUUCAACCCUGGCUACUCCGACAACUCCACAGUUGUUUACUUUGACAAUGGGACAGUCUUUGUGGUUCAGUGGGACCACGUUUAUCUCCAAGGCUGGGAAGACAAGGGCAGUUUCACCUUCCAGGCAGCUCUGCACCAUGACGGCCGCAUUGUCUUUGCCUAUAAAGAGAUCCCUAUGUCUGUCCCGGAAAUCAGCUCCUCCCAGCAUCCUGUCAAAACCGGCCUAUCGGAUGCCUUCAUGAUUCUCAAUCCAUCCCCGGAUGUGCCAGAAUCUCGGCGAAGGAGCAUCUUUGAAUAUCACCGCAUAGAGCUGGACCCCAGCAAGGUCACCAGCAUGUCGGCCGUGGAGUUCACCCCAUUGCCGACCUGCCUGCAGCAUAGGAGCUGUGACGCCUGCAUGUCCUCAGACCUGACCUUCAACUGCAGCUGGUGCCAUGUCCUCCAGAGGUCCCUCAACAACCAGGAUGAAAACACAUGCUCCAGUGGCUUUGACCGCUAUCGCCAGGAGUGGAUGGACUAUGGCUGUGCACAGGAGGCAGAGGGCAGGAUGUGCGAGGACUUCCAGGAUGAGGACCACGACUCAGCCUCCCCUGACACUUCCUUCAGCCCCUAUGAUGGAGACCUCACCACUACCUCCUCCUCCCUCUUCAUCGACAGCCUCACCACAGAAGAUGACACCAAGUUGAAUCCCUAUGCAGGAGGAGACGGCCUUCAGAACAACCUGUCCCCCAAGACAAAGGGCACUCCUGUGCACCUGGGCACCAUCGUGGGCAUCGUGCUGGCAGUCCUCCUCGUGGCGGCCAUCAUCCUGGCUGGAAUUUACAUCAAUGGCCACCCCACAUCCAAUGCUGCGCUCUUCUUCAUCGAGCGUAGACCUCACCACUGGCCAGCCAUGAAGUUUCGCAGCCACCCUGACCAUUCCACCUAUGCGGAGGUGGAGCCCUCGGGCCAUGAGAAGGAGGGCUUCAUGGAGGCUGAGCAGUGCUGAGAACACCAAGUCUCCCCUUUGAAGACUUUGAGGCCACAGAAAAGACAGUUAAAGCAAAGAAGAGAAGUGACUUUUCCUGGCCUCUCCCAGCAUGCCCUGGGCUGAGAUGAGAUGGUGGUUUAUGGCUCCAGAGCUGCUGCUCGCUUCGUCAGCACACCCCGAAUAUUGAAGAGGGGGCCAAAAAACAACCACAUGGAUUUUUUAUAGGAACAACAACCUAAUCUCAUCCUGUUUUGAUGCAAGGGUUCUCUUCUGUGUCUUGUAACCAUGAAACAGCAGAAGAACUAACAUAACUAACUCCAUUUUUGUUUAAGGGGCCUUUACCUAUUCCUGCACCUAGGCUAGGAUAACUUUAGAGCACUGACAUAAAACGCAAAAACAGGAAUCAUGCCGUUUGCAAAACUAACUCUGGGAUUAAAGGGGAAGCAUGUAAACAGCUAACUGUUUUUGUUAAAGAUUUAUAGGAAUGAGGAGGUUUGGCUAUUGUCACAUGACAGACUGUUAGCCAAGGACAAAGAAGUUCUGCAAACCUCCCCUGGACCCUUGCUGGUGUCCAGAUGUCUGCGGUUGUCAGCCCCUUCCUUUCCCCCGACCUAAACAUAAAAGACAAGGCAAAGCCCGCAUAAUUUUAAGACGGUUCUUUAGGACAUUAGUCCACCAUCUUCUUGGUUUGCUGGCUCUCCGAAAUAAAGUCCCUUUCCUUGCUCCAACUCCUUGUCUCUCAACGUAUUGGCUAUGACGCAGCAAGCAGAAUGAAUUUGGACUCAGUUACAGGCUGUCAAUGGUCUGCUCUGUAGCAGUCUCAGAGCCUCCCCGACCCACUACCUGGAGAUAGCCAGAUAGCCAGAUGCCCUGCUCCUGGCCACCUUUAAAGCCCCUGCAUAUGACACAGGUUAACUAAAGUCAAGAUUGGGGCUGCUGCAUUCCAGGUUCCCUAGACUCACAAGCUGGUCCUUGGCCAGGUGCAGUGGCUCACGCCUGUAAUCCCAGCACUUUGGGAGGCUGAGGCAGGCGGAUCACCUGAAGUCAGAAGUUUGAGACCAGCCUGGCCAACAUAAUUAAAAUGUCUCUACUAAAAAUACAAAAAAUUAGCUGGGUGUGGUGACGCUUGCCUGUAUCCCAGCUACUCAGGAAGCUGAGACACGAGAAUCACUUGAACCUGGGAGGCAGAGGUUGCAGUGAGCUCAGAUAGUGCCACUGCACUCCAGCCUGGGUGACAGAGCGAGACUCCGUCUCAAAAAAAAAAAAAGAAAGCAGAUCCUCAUGGCUAUAGAGUUGGCAUUUUAGCCCCAGCUUCUGUAGCUCUGAAAGCCUAAAGAAGGUAUUCUCUCCAUCUGUUAAACACAGUAUAGUGGCUCUCAGCCCUUGGGGCAUGUUAUCAUGGGAGGGAAGUCAAAUAAGAGGAGAGAAAAGAACUCAAGGGGGAAACUGCAUUUUUAGGCUUUGCUCUCUUACCUUGCCCUUUCUACUCAGAACCAAUAACUUCUGCAUCAAAACAUGUUACAGCCUGCAUCAAGGGCUUUACCCCAACCUGCAGCCCAGCCUUCCCUGGGUGAGCUUGCUAUGCGCAGCCACAUUUACCAUGUGGGGCUCCCUAUUCUGAUGGCCUGUUCGGUGCCGGGUUUACUCACUGCCCUGUUCUGAUGUCAGUGCCUGUACAUACCUCCAAAGGCAGGACUUGCCUGAUAAAUAUUUUUCCUCCUCUGAACUGGAUUUUAUAGGCAUUAAAGACAAGUCGGGUGGCUAGAGGGCUCCUUGAGACAUACCUAGCAGGGAACUGCAGGUGGAUUCUGUUGAGAGGCAAAGCACCUGAGUGGUUGGGACACAGGCAGCUGGCAUGGGAGGGACUUUUUUUGAGACAGGGUCUCACUGUGUCGCCCAGGGCAAGGAUGCCCAAAGACACCAGGUUGGAGAGGCACCUGCCAACUACUUGCUUUCCCUGGAGCCUGCAUGUGCCUGUGGGGUGGGGAGGCGUAGGGGUCUACGGCUGCCUGAGAUGGGUGUGCACAGUGUGUGAAGUACCUACCUCCUUGCCUUGCUGGACUGUCAGCCAGUCGCAGGGCCGGCCACAAGACCCAUGUCUCCAUCUGGUCAUACUCCAUAGCUACCAAGUUAACCUGCUCUAAACUUUGGAGAACUGGAUCUGUCCAAUAAACGCUUAUUUGGCCAAGCCUGAUGGCUCGUGCCUGUACUCCCAGCACUUUGGGAGGCUGAGGUGGGAGGGUUGCUUGAGCCCAGGGGUUUGAGACCAGCUUGGGCAACAACAACAAAAAUGCCAGGUGUGGUGGGGUGCACCUGUAGUCCCAGCUACUAGGGAGGCUGAGCCAGGAGGAUCACUUGAGCCCGGGAGGUUGAGGCUGCAGUGGGGGGUCAUAAUCAUGCCACUGUACUCCAGCCUGGGUGACAGAGUGAGACCCUGUCUCCGAAAAAAAAAAAAAAAAAAAGAACGGAAAAAGAAAUGCUUACAUUGUCAGGGAUCCUGUAGACAAUCAUUAACUCUAUGAGAUGCUUGGUUCUAUUUUUUUGGGAGACUUUGUCCAAGUGUUUUGGCUUAAGAAAUCCAUAGGCCUCUCUUGGUGACACAUCUCUAGUACUUUUUGUCAUAAACAAACAGGCCAUCUGCCGCCAAAUACAUCCACUCCCCAUGCCACUGACAUCCUAUGGGUCAGCCAGGCUUGCUUUGACUGAGGCCGAGGCAUCUGGAACUUUCUCUGCCUGCAGGGGCUAGCAGCAGAGGCUUCACCGCAUCACCACCCCUUCCUCCACUCCUGACAUUCUUUCCCUUCAGGGAUCCAAAAUGGUUGGCCGAGCUCCCAGUGGGAAAACGUGUGCUAGAGUUGGGGAGUGAGAUGAGUGGUGCUGUCCAUGGAAUCAGGCCACAGCAGGAACUGCCCCACUGGCCAUUUGAGACACACACAGGUGGUAAAUGCUCUGCUGGUGGGCUGUGCUUCCCUCAUUCAGAGAGCUCUGUUACAGCCCACUGUGUCCUUUAGAAGCUUGAAAGGAACCCAACUCUUUGCUGCACUGUCCUUUUUCUUCCUCAAAUUCAGACCCUCCUUCCACCGGCACCCCCCUACUCCACCCUCAGCUCUUCCUUGCCUGGUUUAUCAAGCAGAGCUGAGGCCCCACGUUUCCAACUCUGAUUGUCACUUGCAUCUUCACAAAGGAUAAACCACGGAGCAACUGGAAAACCAUCAGCCAAGCGUUCGGAUGAGUCUGGUUAUUGGUCCACCCCCGACCAGAUUCCCUUACACUUAACUCACUUCUUUCUUUGGCAAUGACCCUCAUGACAUGUAUAAAUGGGUAUGACUAAGAAGAGGCUGUGAUCUAACAUUUAUUUGCUGCCAUUUUUUACUCUGGGGAGAAGCAGCCCCAACUCAUCACUGGGAAAGAACUCCCCCUGCAAACCAGCUAAAUUUGAUAAUUUAAACCCCCUGCCCCUAAAACUUCUCACAGAGCUGGGGAGUUGGUGGCAACUUUCCAAGUCAAGGUCUUGCUUAGAAAGUCCUUCACUACAUGGCCAGGUGCAGUGGCUCACGCCUGUAGUCCCAGGUACUUGGGAGCCUGAGGCAGGAGGAUUGCUUGAGCUCAGGAGUUCAAGGCUGCAGAGAGCUAUGAUCAUCCCACUGCAUUUGUUUAAAAAUAAAUUUUUAAAAUUUGUGUGUUUUAUCAGGGGUCUCCUGUACAGUGUAUCUGUGUAUGUUUGUGUGUGUGUUUGUAUACAGCCUUGUUUAAUGUUUUGAGCAAUAAGAUAUGCACACACAGGUAUUUUGUUGCUAAAGAGAUUGGACAAGGUUGUAGCUGUGCUCAGGCUUCAGCUUGGUUUGUUAAAUUGAGAGAUAAACAAUGACAAGAGCUGCCAGCCAACCACACUAUUCAAAAAGCAAAGUGUUCACCACUAAAGCUAACCAUUCAUCUGGUUGCAGGCAAGGCUAAGGCUCUCUCUCCUCUAGUUCCUGGAACAGACUCACAGAUUGGCAUGAAGCACUGAUCAGGGGCUGCACUCAGACUCCCUGGCCAAGCAAACCUACACCAGAAGAGUCAGUGUCACAGAUAUGAUGCGGCCAAUCUCUGUCUCCAAAAACCUACCUGAACUUAAUGGUAGAAUUCAAAGAUCUGGGGACUGAGGGCACCCAGCCUUCUAAAACACAAUGUAUUCAUGUGUUUAGUGUAAACUCUCUGCAUGGAUUCUCAGUGUUAAUAAUAAAAGGAAGCAUUCUUUUACAACUCCUGCUGUGUGCAAAAGAAAGUGCAAAGGAUUUGGAGUGGCAUUCCGAAGAUCACCACACAUACCUUGGUUCUGAUGGCUGCUGAACUCCGACUUCUUCGCUGAGACAUGACUGUGGGAACAGCCUCCAGCUAUCUGCUCAUCAGAGGUGCUUUCCUCAACCUCCUGCACCACCUCCAAGAGAAACAGCCUAAAAAGAAACCCCAGCUGUUUACUUAUAUUGGUCUGUAAAUCCCUGGAAGUAAACCCCAUGCAUUUUUAUCUACUGUCUGAGGACAUACAAUAAAUCUGAGAAAGUC